GGAGUAGGGGACAGGUUAGGAUCCUGCCCCAGACUCUGACCCUCUUAAAGGCUCUUGACCAGUAAAAUGUAACCUCUGGGGUCUUAAUGCUGUCUUCACUUCAUCACUUUUACCCCCUUCCCCCACCCCUCCAAUCCUUAUUUCCAUUCCCCCUCCCUCCUCUGCUGUCCAUCACCUAUAUCUUUCCCCCCAUAUGGUGUCCGUUCCUUAUAUGAGUCCCCCUUCUGUCCUUCCCCUAUAUCAGUCCCCUCUCUGGUGUUCAUUGCCUCUCUCUUAUCUCUUUUCUAUGUGGUCGCUCCCUUAUAUCUCUAUCACUUCUUUACUAGUCCGUCUUGACCCCUUCUCAUAGCCUCCGCAUUAGGUCUGCCUCCUUUGCUCUGACACAUGUCCAGUCGAGCCCUUCAGGUGUAUUCCCUUGCCCCUGGGCAUUUACCAUCAUUUCUGCCUCCUUUUCUAUCUACUCCUAUUAUUUGUCUCCCAGACCAUUCCUUGUCACCACAAGUCUGUGCCUACCCACUUUCCCUUAAUACCUCAACUCUUAUUAUCAUUUCUCUUUUCUUGUCUCCUCUACUUAUUGGGGUGUUGGAGAUUUGGGGUACAAAGACACAGGUUUUGAUGAUUAGAACAAGGGAUCCCCAUCUCAGCCCUUGAGGGAUUUCUCAUCCUAGUAAAAAUUUCCCGUUUCUCAGCCAUGUUGCUCUGCCUCUUGCAUCUGCCUCCCAGAAUCAUUCUUCACCAAGUCCAGACAGUAUGUGUGUGUGUGUUUCUAGAGUUGUUCCUAAGUUCCCUGCUGCCAGGAGAAAGAUGCCCUCUGAAGUCUAACCCGCCUCCCUUGGCUGCAGCCUGAACCAGCCCUUUCCCCAAAUGCUUAUGUGUAUCAACAGAUUUCUCCUCUGGGUAUACCAAGUGUCUAAGUGCGGUGGGCAUGUUGCCUGCAAUGUCUGUAGUUUCAGAGGCUAGGUAUUGGUGAUCUCUGUAUCUAGAGAACAUUAGUUAGUCUCUGAGAUGGGUUGAGAUAGAGUUUCAAAGUAUGUGGUUUCUAAAUGGUGGACAUUCUGAGGGUUCAUCGCUCACUGUGAUCUGGAGGUUGGGUAAAUUUGAGAGACAUAUUUAUAGACAGAAAAGGGCUGAAUUUGCAAAACUCUGCUACUCAGUGCAUUCUGUUGGAAUGAAGCUCAAAGACCAGUUCUCCUGCAGUAUACUCAUGGUUAUCCCAUAAAGGUGACAGAGUUUGAUCUUUUUUCCAUCUAAAAUCUGAUACCUUAAGCCUAAUUUCUAGCUCUUUGCUGUCGCCAAUGUGACAUCUCUCUUACUUCAAUAGGGCCUGUGUGGCAUUGGGGUUUAAAGGAGAGGCAGUUUGCAGGGAGAGCGGCAUGGCAAGAACAACAGAGCUGGGGAAGGAGGACCCUGGUCUCAUCUCAGCCAUAGGCGACACUUGGUCUACUGUUCUCUCUUCUCAAAGUUUUGUUCCCAUCUCCAGCUCUUGUCUUUGGAGGCCCCUCUGUGUCACCAGGCCUGGAUAUUCCAUUCUUUCCCCCUGACAUCUUUCUUCCUCAAGCUCCUCACUGUGCCUUGAGAAGGCUCCUGACCUAUGGAGUGGCUUCCAUCCUGUCCACUGAGACUAGGUGGGGUGAGGUGGUGGGGGCAGUGUUGAAUCUCUGGGCACUGAAUGGGAGAAGAGAUAAAUUUGGUCUCUACUUGUCCAAACAAGGGCAUAUUUCCCACCUUCUGCCCUGGGGCCUCCACAGCCAGAUGCCGACAAAAGCCAUCUUCUCCUUACCACCAGAAGAACCAGAACUUUCCCUAAAGGAUGAGCAGGGUUGAACUAGGGGAGGAGGGCACAGAGGAGGGAAGAGUUGGGAGGGGAGGCCCUCUCAUGUCUCUGACUGUGAACAGAUGUACGGGGACCCUCUAUGCACCGAACCCAAUACGUUCAUUCCCCGUAUGAUCGUCCUGGUUGGAACCCUCGGUUCUGCAUCAUCUCGGGGAACCAGCUGCUCAUGCUGGAUGAGGAUGAGAUACACCCCCUACUGAUCCGGGACCGGAGGAGCGAGUCCAGUCGCAACAAACUGCUGAGACGCACAGUCUCCGUGCCGGUGGAGGGGCGGCCCCACGGCGAGCAUGAAUACCACUUGGGUCGCUCGAGGAGGAAGAGUGUCCCAGGGGGGAAGCAGUACAGCAUGGAGGGUGCCCCUGCUGCGCCCUUCCGGCCCUCGCAAGGCUUCCUGAGCCGACGGCUAAAAAGCUCCAUCAAACGAACGAAGUCACAACCCAAACUUGACCGGACCAGCAGCUUUCGCCAGAUCCUGCCUCGCUUCCGAAGUGCUGACCAUGACCGGGCCCGGCUGAUGCAAAGCUUUAAGGAGUCACACUCUCAUGAGUCCUUGCUGAGUCCUAGCAGUGCAGCUGAGGCAUUGGAGCUCAACUUGGAUGAAGAUUCCAUUAUCAAGCCAGUGCACAGCUCCAUCCUGGGCCAGGAGUUCUGUUUUGAGGUAACAACUUCAUCAGGAACAAAAUGCUUUGCCUGUCGGUCUGCGGCCGAAAGAGACAAAUGGAUUGAGAAUCUGCAGCGGGCAGUAAAGCCCAACAAGGACAACAGCCGCCGGGUAGACAAUGUGCUAAAGCUGUGGAUCAUAGAGGCCCGGGAGCUGCCCCCCAAGAAGCGGUACUACUGUGAGCUCUGCCUGGAUGACAUGCUGUAUGCACGCACCACCUCCAAGCCCCGCUCUGCCUCUGGGGACACCGUCUUCUGGGGCGAGCACUUCGAGUUUAACAACCUGCCGGCUGUCCGUGCCCUGCGGCUGCAUCUGUACCGUGACUCAGACAAAAAGCGCAAGAAGGACAAGGCAGGCUAUGUCGGCCUGGUGACUGUGCCAGUGGCCACCCUGGCUGGGCGCCACUUCACAGAGCAGUGGUACCCUGUAACCCUGCCAACAGGCAGUGGGGGAUCUGGGGGCAUGGGUUCGGGAGGGGGAGGGGGCUCGGGGGGUGGCUCAGGGGGCAAGGGCAAAGGAGGUUGCCCGGCUGUGCGGCUGAAAGCACGUUACCAGACAAUGAGCAUCUUGCCCAUGGAGCUAUAUAAAGAGUUUGCAGAGUAUGUCACCAACCAUUAUCGGAUGCUGUGUGCAGUCUUGGAGCCCGCCCUGAAUGUCAAAGGCAAGGAGGAGGUUGCCAGUGCACUAGUUCACAUCCUGCAGAGUACAGGCAAGGCCAAGGACUUCCUUUCAGACAUGGCCAUGUCUGAGGUAGACCGGUUCAUGGAACGGGAGCACCUCAUAUUCCGCGAGAACACGCUUGCCACUAAAGCCAUAGAAGAGUAUAUGAGACUGAUUGGUCAGAAAUACCUCAAGGAUGCCAUUGGAGAAUUCAUCCGUGCUCUGUAUGAAUCUGAGGAAAACUGCGAGGUAGACCCUAUCAAGUGCACAGCAUCCAGUUUGGCAGAGCACCAGGCCAACCUGCGAAUGUGCUGUGAGUUGGCCCUGUGCAAGGUGGUCAACUCCCACUGCGUGUUCCCGAGGGAGCUGAAGGAGGUGUUUGCUUCGUGGCGGCUGCGCUGCGCAGAGCGAGGCCGGGAGGACAUCGCAGACAGGCUUAUCAGCGCCUCACUCUUCCUGCGCUUCCUCUGCCCAGCGAUUAUGUCGCCCAGUCUCUUUGGGCUUAUGCAGGAGUACCCAGAUGAGCAGACCUCACGAACCCUCACCCUCAUUGCCAAGGUCAUCCAGAACCUGGCCAACUUUUCCAAGUUUACCUCAAAGGAGGACUUUCUGGGCUUCAUGAAUGAGUUUCUGGAGCUGGAAUGGGGUUCCAUGCAGCAGUUUUUGUAUGAGAUCUCCAAUCUGGACACGCUAACCAACAGCAGUAGCUUUGAGGGUUACAUCGACUUGGGCCGAGAGCUCUCCACACUGCAUGCCCUACUCUGGGAGGUGCUGCCCCAGCUCAGCAAGGAAGCCCUCCUGAAGCUGGGUCCACUGCCCCGGCUCCUCAACGACAUCAGCACAGCUCUGAGGAACCCCAACAUCCAAAGGCAGCCAAGCCGCCAGAGUGAGCGGCCCCGGCCUCAGCCUGUGGUACUGCGGGGGCCAUCGGCUGAGAUGCAGGGCUACAUGAUGCGGGACCUCAACAGCUCCAUCGACCUUCAGUCCUUCAUGGCUCGAGGCCUCAACAGCUCUAUGGACAUGGCUCGCCUCCCCUCCCCAACCAAGGAAAAGCCACCCCCACCACCGCCUGGUGGUGGUAAAGACCUGUUCUAUGUAAGCCGUCCACCCCUGGCCCGUUCCUCACCAGCAUACUGCACGAGCAGCUCGGACAUCACAGAGCCAGAGCAGAAGAUGCUGAGUGUCAACAAGAGUGUGUCCAUGCUGGACUUACAGGGUGAUGGGCCUGGUGGCCGCCUCAACAGCAGCAGUGUUUCGAACCUGGCGGCCGUAGGGGACCUGCUGCACUCAAGCCAGGCCUCGCUGACAGCAGCCUUGGGGCUACGGCCUGCGCCUGCCGGACGCCUCUCCCAGGGGAGUGGCUCAUCCAUCACGGCGGCUGGCAUGCGCCUCAGCCAGAUGGGUGUCACCACAGACGGUGUCCCUGCCCAGCAACUGCGAAUCCCCCUCUCCUUCCAGAACCCUCUCUUCCACAUGGCUGCUGAUGGGCCAGGUCCCCCAGGCGGCCAUGGAGGGGGCGGUGGCCAUGGCCCACCUUCCUCCCAUCACCACCACCACCACCAUCACCACCACCGAGGUGGAGAGCCCCCUGGGGACACCUUUGCCCCAUUCCAUGGCUAUAGCAAGAGUGAGGACCUCUCUUCCGGGGUCCCCAAGCCCCCUGCUGCCUCCAUCCUUCAUAGCCACAGCUACAGUGAUGAGUUUGGACCCUCUGGCACUGACUUCACCCGUCGGCAGCUUUCACUCCAGGACAACCUGCAGCACAUGCUGUCCCCUCCCCAGAUCACCAUUGGUCCCCAGAGGCCAGCCCCCUCAGGGCCUGGAGGUGGGAGCGGUGGGGGCAGCGGUGGGGGUGGCGGGGGCCAGCCGCCUCCAUUGCAGAGGGGCAAGUCUCAGCAGUUGACAGUCAGCGCAGCCCAGAAACCCCGGCCAUCCAGCGGGAAUCUAUUGCAGUCCCCAGAGCCAAGUUAUGGCCCCGCCCGUCCACGGCAACAGAGCCUCAGCAAGGAGGGCAGCAUUGGGGGCAGCGGGGGCAGCGGUGGCGGAGGGGGUGGGGGGCUGAAGCCCUCCAUCACCAAGCAGCAUUCUCAGACACCAUCCACAUUGAACCCCACAAUGCCAGCCUCUGAGCGGACAGUGGCCUGGGUCUCCAACAUGCCUCACCUGUCGGCUGACAUCGAGAGUGCCCACAUCGAGCGGGAAGAGUACAAGCUCAAGGAGUACUCAAAAUCGAUGGAUGAGAGCCGGCUGGAUAGGGUGAAGGAGUACGAGGAGGAGAUUCACUCACUGAAAGAGCGGCUGCACAUGUCCAACCGGAAGCUGGAAGAGUAUGAGCGGAGGCUGCUGUCCCAGGAAGAACAAACCAGCAAAAUCCUGAUGCAGUAUCAGGCCCGACUGGAGCAGAGUGAGAAGAGGCUAAGGCAGCAGCAGGCAGAGAAGGAUUCCCAGAUCAAGAGCAUCAUUGGCAGGCUGAUGCUGGUGGAGGAGGAGCUGCGCCGGGACCACCCCGCCAUGGCUGAGCCGCUGCCAGAACCCAAGAAGAGGCUGCUCGACGCUCAGGUGGAGAGGCAGCUUCCCCCCUUGGGUCCAACAAACCCGCGUGUGACGCUGGCCCCACCGUGGAAUGGCCUGGCCCCCCCAGCCCCACCACCCCCACCCCGGCUGCAGAUUACGGAGAACGGCGAGUUCCGAAACACCGCAGACCACUAGCCCACCCAGCAUCAGAGACCUUCUCUUCCUUUCCUGUGCACCCCACCCUGUAACAGCACCAACCACCAGGAUUGGACAUCACCGAGGAACAGCGGGAUUGCCUCCCCGAAUGCCUCCCUGGGAGGCACACUGAUUGCCCACCCCCACCACUGCACCAUUUCCAGGAGGGAGAGUGGGGACCCUCAGCCGCCCCCUUUUCCUUCCCAUUGGGGUGCUGCCCUCUCUUUGACCCCCAGGGACCCUUGCCCCAGGACACCGCCUACCCCGUACAGACCCCUUCACUCCGGGGUGCUAUCCCCAUCCUCUGCCUCAUCGUUCCCCUGAGCACUGGGGGACAGACCCUCACCCCCACCCUGGGGGUGUGGCACCUCCAAACUUUCAACUUCAGGGUGAUUUUUUUAGCAGUAACCAGAGCUGACAAUCUAACUCCCCUCCACCGCCCCAUUUUGGCCUCCCCUGCCCCCCUUGUUAUGGGGAGGGGACCCCGGGUGAGGGGGCCCUAUUACCCCUUGAUUUCUCAGGAGCGUCUGGGGGGGCUCAGCACGCACAAACUCCUUCUCCUUCUACCACUCUUAAAUUUACUCCCUCCCCACCCAGAACCCAGAUGGGGUGGAGGGGGCCACCGGGGCAGGGAGGGGGCGGCAAGGGGGGAAUGGGAGUUGUCUCCCCUUCUCCCCACACCUGAUCUGCUCUCGGCUGGUCCCAGAGCGGGGUGAGGGGGCUUAUGCCCCCCCCUCCCCCAGUGUGUUGGGUGGGGUGGAAUUGAGGUUAGGGUGAGGGGUCAGGGUUUAGGAGGGUGUGUAUGUUGGGAGGACAGGCUAGUUGAUCUGUCCUACUCUGACACACAGUCCCCUCUGCCCCUUCCUUCUCUCUUCUUGGUCUCUACUCCCAGGGGGAGGGGGGAACUUACUCUAGGAAAAGCCAUGUCUCUCUCCCCCAGGGUGGGGGGACCUGUGUUGGAGGAGGGGUGUUGGGGGGCCCCCUUCCAUGACUCUGUCCCCUGGGGGAGGUAGGACAGGGCUGGGCUUCCCUCUCAUCCUCCCCCUCCCAAUCUCCUUCCACCUCCCUCCCUCCCGCCAGCUCCACGAUUUUUCGGUGUUUCUCUGUACAUAGUUUUCUGGCGGGAUAGGGGAGGUAGGAUGGAUGGGGUUUGGGGUGGGUAGGCCAUGGGAGGGGAGAAGCCCCUCCUUGGCACCCCCUCUUCCCUGACUGCUGUCCCCUACCCAGCCUUGCCCCCUUCAUCCUUUUGCGUUUGGUAUUGAGACUCUCCUAGACUCUACUCCUCUUUCUUUUGUAUGGACAGUUCCCCUUCAGUCCCAUCCCCCUACACAUACACCCAGCCGGGGCCAAAUUUAUACUUAUAUAAAAGUUGUAAAUAUGUGAAAUUUUAUCCCUGUGCCCUUUCCCCACCUCAGGCCCUACCCCUGGACCCUCCCCAACCUUCCUUCUCUCUUCUUUGGCUGUUGUAAUUAUCUGGGGUUUGUACUGUACAUAUCCGGGGUGUGUGUGUGUGGGCUGGGGGCAACCCUUCUGUACAGAGCUUCCUGGCCCCCUCCCCCCCCGCCCCUCUGCUUCCCUCCCCACCCACCACCUCAAGGGUAGGGAGUUGCUCUUCCUACCUGUUUUAUUUUGUUUUCUCGUUCUCCCUCCCCACCCCACUCCCAGCCUUAUCUAUCCCCCCUCACUGUCCCCUUUUCUCCACUCCCAGCCCCAUUUCCUUUUUUUCUGGAGUGUGUGGUGAAACAGAAAAAAACAUGUUUAAUAAACGGAGAUUGUUCUUUUA